GUUGCAGCACAGUCCCUGGCAGAGCCAGAGCCUCUCCGCGCAGCCCAGCCCGAGCGCCGAGCGCCGCGCGCCGCCGCCACUGCAGCUCGCGGCCCCUUCGCCUUCGCCCGCCUUUCCCGCGGCUGAUUUGCCUUAAACUCCCUAAAAUCUCCGCAGCUCUGGUUCCUGUUGCGGCCGGUAAGUAUUUGCCAGUUGUGGGGCUAUUUGCGCAACUUUGGCCCAGGCCGGAGGGCGACGGGCCGCGGGCCUGGCGGAGUGCGGGGCCGGAGGGGCGCCGAUCCGUGCGGGGAGCCGGAGCGCGGCGGACGCGCUGCGAGGACCCGGUGACGGGCGGCUGCCAGGCCGCCUGCUUGUUGCCGGCGCGUCAGGUCCCGGGCGUGCGGCCUCCCUGAGUCGGAGGCGAAGCCCCUACGGAGACUAGUUCCCAAAUUAGUUACCUUCUUUUCUUUCUUUCUCUGCCUUUAUUUUUUUCGAGGGGGGAGGGGAGGUGUAGACGGGAGGCGGGAGAACCCGGUUGAUUGACGUGCCUAGAGCCCGCUUCUCUCAACUUACAGCUGCGGCUCGGCGGCGGGUGGGAGGGGAAGUGUCCCGGAGCCCGAGGCUGCAGACUUGGGCGCGCUCCGAGGGAGGAGGCGUAAGAUCCGUGCAAAUUCUUGUUACGCUGUUUCCCACCCCCUCUCGCCGGCACACACGCUUUUUGUUCAGUAAAAAGUGGAAGGUCUGAGUUUGGGAAUUUUAAGUGGAAAAGAUCUGUUUCUUGGGAAGGGAGUGCUUUCGCUUGCAGCGGUGGGCGCUUACUAGAAGUUCGGUAAAUGUGUUGGAUGCAGAUCGGGAGUCGUUACUACUAAAGUAUGUAGGCAGGGUCUGAGCUCAGCCACCCCACCCAGUCUCCCUUUCUACCUAAGCAACGCGUGUACAUGAUCUGAAGGGUUGACAUGACAUUUUCUAAAUUGGGCGAAUCAGGAAGAGGUUGAUGAAAAUCCUUGACGUUUUCUGGGGAUAGGACAUUUGUGUGUGAUAACGUUCUUAAGUCGAAUUUCAGUGUGGCAGUGCACGCAGAUUCUUCAUUGGUGUUAGUGUAUUUCCAUACGGUCUCUAAUUAACAGAAGAUGGCAAAGCCCAGCCACAGCAGCUAUGUCCUUCAGCAGCUAAACAACCAAAGAGAAUGGGGUUUUCUCUGUGACUGCUGUAUUGCAAUUGAUGACAUUUACUUUCAAGCACACAAGGCAGUUCUAGCUGCCUGUAGCUCCUAUUUUAGAAUGUUUUUCAUGAACCAUCAGCAUAGUACUGCACAACUGAAUCUCAGCAACAUGAAAAUUAGUGCAGAAUGUUUUGAUCUCAUUUUGCAGUUUAUGUAUUUAGGAAAAAUUAUGACAGCUCCCUCCAGUUUUGAGCAGUUUAAAGUGGCAAUGAACUACCUACAGCUAUACAAUGUUCCUGACUGUUUAGAAGACAUCCAGGAUGCAGAUUGUUCUAGUUCAAAAUGUUCCUCUUCUGCUUCCAGCAAACAGAACAGCAAAAUGAUAUUUGGGGUAAGAAUGUAUGAAGAUACUGUGGCUCGAAAUGGCAAUGAAGCCAACAGGUGGUGUGCAGAGCCAAGUUCAACGGUAAAUACACCACAUAAUAGAGAGGCUGAUGAAGAGUCUUUACAAUUAGGUAAUUUUCCUGAGCCACUAUUUGAUGUAUGUAAAAAAAGUUCCGUGUCCAAAUUAUCUACUCCAAAAGAACGUGUGUCAAGACGCUUUGGGCGGAGUUUUACCUGUGAUAGCUGUGGAUUUGGCUUUAGCUGUGAAAAAUUAUUAGAUGAGCAUGUGCUAACCUGUACUAACAGACAUUUAUACCAAAACACAAGAUCUUACCAUAGAAUAGUAGAUAUUAGAGAUGGAAAAGACAGUAACAUCAAAGCUGAAUUUGGUGAAAAAGAUUCUUCCAAAACAUUUUCUGCACAGACGGACAAAUACAGAGGAGACACAAGCCAGGCUGCUGAUGAUUCAGCUUCAACCACUGGAAGCAGAAAAAGUAGCACAGUGGAGUCUGAAAUAGCAAGCGAAGAGAAAAGCAGAGCUGCUGAGAGGAAAAGGAUUAUUAUUAAGAUGGAGCCAGAAGAUAUUCCUACAGAUGAACUGAAAGACUUUAACAUUAUUAAAGUUACUGAUAAAGACUGUAAUGAAUCCACUGACAAUGAUGAAUUAGAAGAUGAACCUGAAGAGCCAUUUUAUAGAUACUAUGUUGAAGAAGAUGUCAGCAUAAAAAAAAGUGGUAGGAAAACUCUAAAACCUCGAAUGUCAGUAAGUGCUGAUGAAAGAGGUGGUUUAGAGAAUAUGAGGCCCCCUAACAACAGCAGUCCAGUACAAGAGGAUGCUGAAAAUGCAUCUUGUGAGCUGUGUGGACUUACAAUAACCGAGGAGGACCUGUCAUCUCAUUACUUAGCCAAACACAUUGAAAAUAUCUGUGCAUGUGGUAAAUGUGGACAAAUACUUGUAAAGGGUAGGCAGCUUCAGGAACAUGCUCAACGAUGUGGCGAGCCCCAAGAUCUGACCAUGAAUGGGUUAGGAAAUACUGAGGAGAAAAUGGACUUGGAAGAGAAUCCUGAUGAGCAGUCCGAAAUAAGAGAUAUGUUUGUUGAAAUGCUGGAUGAUUUUAGGGACAAUCAUUACCAGAUAAACAGUAUCCAAAAAAAGCAGUUAUUUAAACAUUCUGCCUGCCCUUUUCGAUGUCCUAAUUGUGGCCAGCGUUUUGAAACUGAAAAUCUAGUGGUUGAACAUAUGUCUAGCUGCUUAGAUCAAGAUAUGUUUAAGAGUGCCAUCAUGGAAGAAAAUGAAAGAGAUCACAGACGAAAGCAUUUUUGUAAUCUGUGUGGAAAAGGAUUUUAUCAGCGGUGUCACUUAAGAGAACACUAUACUGUUCAUACUAAGGAAAAACAGUUUGUUUGUCAAACAUGUGGAAAGCAGUUUUUAAGAGAGCGUCAGUUGCGACUGCACAAUGAUAUGCACAAAGGCAUGGCCAGGUAUGUCUGUUCCAUUUGUGAUCAAGGAAACUUCAGAAAACAUGACCAUGUACGGCAUAUGAUUUCUCAUUUAUCUGCUGGUGAGACUAUAUGCCAGGUCUGCUUUCAGAUAUUCCCAAAUAAUGAACAGUUGGAGCAGCACAUGGAUGUUCAUCUGUAUACAUGUGGAAUAUGUGGAGCAAAAUUUAAUUUGAGGAAAGAUAUGAGAUCACAUUAUAAUGCCAAGCAUUUGAAAAGAACCUGAGUGAUUUUCUACUGUACUAAUGUUUAGAUGAUAGCAGAUAAAACACCAAAGCAAAGGAUAUGAGCUAUUUAGGAAUUGAUUAUAUAAGAUGAUUUGUUAGAAACAAAUUUCAAGGCCCUUUUAACUUUAAUAUUUUUGUUUAGGAUUUUAAGUAUCUACAUUUAGGUAUUAAAUGUUUAUCAUUUUUGUUGUUUCUUAAUAGAAUUAUUUGUUUUUAGUUUUUCUUAGCUAUGAUUAAAAUUUUUAAAUGUAGACUACAAGUGGUUGUUACCCAUUCAAUGACUAUUAAACUUUAGUUUUUCAUCAAUAAGGUGAUGACUUCACUAUUUCUAUGUGUUUUUUUUUUUUUAAGGUUAUCCUGUGAAAUUUUAAACCCAGAAUCAUUGGCCAUUUCUGUUUAAAUUUUAAAAAUUCCUUAAGUAAUUAUUUGAAACUAUCCCGUUUGCUUUUAGUGAGUUAACUACUCUUUAUUCCCCCUUAUUAAUGAAAUUCAUAUUCUUAAAUUGACAAGCUUAUUAGGCAAGUUAGGUGCACUGAAUCUAACCUUUAAGGUUGACAUGGGCUCAAACUUGGCCUAAAAAGAUUGAUGAACCUGAGGAAAUUUUUAUAAAUGAAUAUUUCCUAUAAUUGAUAAAAUAUUAUCAUUUAAUUAUCACAUUUAAAACUUAUAUUAAGUGUAAAUUCCAGUGGCUUUACCUCACUUGAAAAAUUAGUGGGGAUAAGCCAUUUUGUUUUGUGAUAUUAAAUUUAACUAUGAUAGUUAAUUAAAAAGACAUAUCUUGUAUUCAUUAAAAAUAUUUUAAUUUAAAAUAUUCUGAUUUCUAAAGUGUGUUAGCUUAUCAAUUAUUUUUGUUUAUAAAUAGACUUUAAUAGCUCUCUAAGAAUAUGACCUCUAAAGGAAAAGAUGAUUUUUUACAAUACAUACUUCUGGAACUUUGAGAUUUGAGAAAGCUUCCAUGUAUAUUGAUAAAUCUAAUAAAAUAAAGAGAUCAAUUAUAAACCUGGUUGUUCUAUAAAAGUAGAGUGCACAAAAAAAUGUCUUGUGUUUUAUACUGUCUAAGAUUUGGAGGAAAUGUGGCAAAUUGCAGUUUAUCGCCAUAUUUUAUUAUCAUUUUUUUCUGUAAAAGACUAUAAAACUUGAGGAUUAUAAAAUAAUCACAGAGUAUAUCAAUGGAAACAGUUUAUCAUUUUUUCAGUUAAAGUAGUAGUAUUGUUAGUUGUUGCUGACACAGGGUCUACAUAAUUACAUGUGAAUUAAAACAUUGGCAAAACUGACCCACCAAUAAACACAUCUAUUGAAUAGAA